AGUAAGCAUAAAGAGGCGAAGGUCCAGGACAGAGAUUUGGAGCACUACAACAUUUAAAGUUUGGGAAAUGAAGAACUAGCAAAGGAAACUUAGAAGGAGAAAUCACUGAGGCAAGAGGAAAACCAGGAGAACAUGGAAUCUUGGAAGCCAAUGAAGAAAGUGUUUUGAGAGGAGGGAGUAAUGAACCCCUUGUCAGAUGCUGCUCAUAGUUCCAGUAAAGAGAACUGGUAAUUGAAUUGGUCAUUCUAGUUUGCAAUGUGGAAUUCAUUAGUGAUUCUGACAAGAGCAGGUUUGAUAGAGUGGUGGGGAAAUAGACUCAUUGGAAUGGAUUCAAGAGAAAGGGAAGUGAGAAAUUGGAGACAUGCAGAAAGAAUCAUUUUUCUGAGGAAUUUUGCUGAAGAGGGAGGGAGAGAAAUAGAAUAGUAACUUAAGAGAGAUGUUCAAAGAGUUUUUUUGUUUUUUGUUUUUGUUUUGACGUGUUUGUAGGAGGCUGAGAAAAAAAUGGAAAAUUUGAUGGGAUAGACGAAGAGGUAGUGGUGGUUAAUGGGGAUCUAGUGUGUAAGUAAAAAGGUUGGGUCUUGGGUAGAGCAGAAAUAGUUCACGCUAGUAAUGAAAGAGGAAUCAGAAUAUGUGGGCACAGACGUAGUUAGGUAGAUGUGGUUUGAGAGUUUGUAGAAGUUCUUUUAUUGCUUCUAGUAUUUUAUUAGUAAAAUAGGACACAGGGUCAUAAGAUAAAAGUGAGGAUGAGAGGGAAGGUGAUGGAAGAUUGAGGAGCAAAAAGUUGAAAUAGUUAUGUAAGAGAGUGGCAGAAUGGAUGAAUCAGGAAAAUAAGGUAUAAUUGUCAGUCAGCAUUAAGGAAACUCAUUUGAGGCUCCUGGCCACGAAUUUAAAGAGAAACCAAUUUAUCAGACAUCGUGUAUUUGUGUGUGUGUGUGUGUGUGUGUGUGUGUGAGAGAGAGAGAGAGAGAGUGCAUGUCCAUCCAGCCACAUGCAGCUGUGUAGGUAUCAACACAGAAUAGGCAGAAAAUUGCGCUGAAAGAGAGAGAGAGAGAGAGAGAGUCCAUCCAGCCACAUGCAGCUCUGUAGGUAUCAACAUAGAAUAGGCAGAAAAUUGCAUUGGUAACAACUAGCCAAGCAAGAUUGACAUAGUCAGAAGGAAGACAAGUAGUUAAGCAUGUAUGCAAAGGAAGGAAGGAAGUAAAUGAUUGAAUAUGGAUUUAAUUUGGGUAAGAAGGGGAUUGAGGACAUGGGAAGGUAAAAGGAAGUGCAGAAGUCAUCAGAUUAGUGGACUACAGGUCUGUUGGGUUGGCAGAUUUUUUGGAGUUAGGAUAUUAGAGGUAGUGAGCUGGUAUCAGAGUGUGAUACUUAAAAAUGGUAUUUCGAGGCUGGGCAUCAUGCCUCAUGUGUGUAAUCCUAGCACUUCGGGAGGCUGAGGCAGGUGGAUCACUUGAGGUCAGGAGAUUGAGACCAGCCUGGCCAACAUGGUGAAACCCCGUCUCUACAAAAAAAUACAAAAAUUAGUCGGGUGUGGUGGUGCGUGCCUGUAGUCCCAGCUACUCAGGAGGCUGAGGUGGGAGGAUCACUUGAGUCCAGUGAGCUGUGAUUGCACCACUGCACUCCAGCCUGGGCGACAGGGUGAGACCCUGUCUCAGAACAAAACAAAACAAAAAAUGGCAUUUUGGAAGGGUUGCAUUUAUUAAAAUUGAGAAGGUUUAAGGUUUGACUGUAUGGGAAUGAGUAUAAAAUAGGGUUGAGGGAAGGAUCAGUGGAAGAUCCUAGAUCUACUGAAGGGCAGAACUUCCUUUCUGAUAAUAAGAAACUGACAAGCAAGAAUUGGGAAAGGAUUGUGUGGAUGAUGAGAUUCCCAAGCAUUAUGAAAAUAAUGAUGGUGUAAUGAGCAAGCAGCUAAAAUCUUCAAGAAAUAAAGUGGAGAGCUUGAUAACUGCAGUAAAGAACGGCUACAGUCUGAUGAUGAGAUUUCAGUUUGGAUGUUUUUAGGGAAGAGUUAGGAAGAAUUGUCUGGAAUGGGCAACUAGGAUUGAGAAAGAAUAGAAGCUUUUAGUCUGAGGAACUGAGCCACCAUUAUCAGGCCUAGAGAGGCACUGAAAUGAAAUAAUUACCUCUGGAAGCCACAUGCUGUGUGGGCUCUAGACUGAUACCAGGUAGCCAUAAAAUGCCAUGUGCUAGACGCCAUAACUCAUACCCUAUAGUUCGACAAUAUAUAGUCAAUCACUAAUCAAUGCUAUUUCUGUAAACCAAUGAGAAUUCCUGUCAAACAAUUGUGUAUCAGUCUGCUCCAUGUCCCCCUUUGCCUUUAAAAACCUGCUGGUAACAAAGGCUGAAUGGGGCACUCCCCAAGGCAACUUGGAAAUGUGUCCUAGGCUGCAGGUCUCAACCUUGGCUCAAAUAAAUUCUCUAUAUUAAUUUUACUUCAGUUUCUUCCUUUAGGUCAGUAGGAUCAAGAAGACCUACCUUCACAUCCAGGCCCUGUGGUAUGAGGAGUUGGGAGGGAAAACACAUAACACUUGAGAAAGCUUCAGGGGAAAUGCCGAUAACAGAGAACCAAGUUGUAGUUAGAGCAAGAAUGACUUUAACUAGUAGAACCAGUGAAGAACAUCCCAAAUAGAGGAAACACCAGAAACAGAGUCACAAAAGGUACAUUAUUUGAUGUUGGAGAAUAGCGACAACUCUAGUGCAGUUUAGAAUUUAAGGUUUAUUCCAGUUUGAUGUCUUCGUAGUCACAUCCCUUUUAGUAUCAUGUAGAAUUUAUAGGCAUUCUCUAUAUUUUAACAUCCAGGAAUUUUUCAUAAGAAUGAACAUCAAUCCCAAUAUUGAAAUAGUAGGACAUGGCUUAAUGCUGAUCCUGAACCAUUAAUAAUGAUUUUUGUUACAGCUUCCCAGCCACUUCUUCAAUUUAGUUGUAGCUCUGGGCAUGCAAUGCGGAAUAAUGACAUCUCUCCUCCCUUAUGAAUCCUACCUCCCACCAAGUCUCUCAGGAAUACCCAAAUCAGAGAAAAAUAUUAAUUAUAAAAAAUAAGCAUAGAGCUCUUUCAUCUCUUUCCCAAAGUAUUUCUAGAAUUUUUUCACCUAGUUUAUAUUACUACAUUUAAAUUACCCACUAAUAGAAUAACAGUGUUCUUAAAAUAUUUUUAGAAAUCCAAGAGACCAUGUUGGUUCUUAAGCACCUUUUGUUGUUCAUCAGCUACAUGUAUUAUAUCACUAAUAUGUUUCAGUUAGGUGUCUUUCAACUUUAGAUAUCAGAAAGCCCAAUUCAAACAACCUUACACAAUGAAGAAAUUUAUUAGCUUAAUGUAACUGGAAGUCCAGAGGAAAGGCAGUCUUUAGGAUUAGUCAGUUAGUACCUUAAUGAAGACACCAAAGAUUCAGAUCAUUUCCAUUGUUCCACUCUGCUGUCCACAGUGCUGGCUUUAUUCCAGGGUGGGAUUCUCAGAUUCUCUUCAUACAGUGGGUACCAGGAAGGAGCUAUAUGUUCUAUAAGGAGGAAAAAUUCUGGCUUCCUCCUAACAGAAAGGACAACCUUAACCAGAGGCCACCAGCAAACCUCUUCUACCUCUUCUCCUAUCUGAUUGACAUGAUUCCUUCUCAUAUCUGAGUCAGUUUCUGGCAGUGAGGAUGGAUCCACCAUUGAGCUAAAGUUAGUUCUCCCAGUUUUUGCCACUCAGAGUUGUGGCGUGGAUAUUGGAGAACACAGUCACAAUGUCUGCUUACAGUGUUUGCCUUGGUUGUGUUCUAAUGCUCUGAGGUUCUUUAUUCAUUCUUAUCUGUUACAUUUUUAUAGUGAGUUAAAAUAUGCUUCAUCAUACUUUAUUGGUUUAAUUGCCAUGUUCAGAGCUUUCUGUCAUAUAGAGAGUAGAGCAAUUAUUAAGCAUUCCUUUCUGCAAAAAGGGAAAAAUGCUGGAAUAGUGAAAAGAUUGAAGAUAGUUGGCAAAUUUGAAUCUGUACCUCCUUAUAACCAAUAGUUUUUAACCUCUUUCAACCUCCAGUAAUUGACUUAGCUAUCAUUUACAUAGAAACUUUAGUAAUUUGAUUUGUAUCUCCUUUCUCUCUGUCAAAAGUUGCCUGAAGCGUUGUGGUAAAGUAGAAAGUGGACUGGGUUGUGAUUAAGUUUCUAAUUAAUUCUAGCUCCACUGCUUUCCAGAUCUGUGUGAUCAUGGGCAGAUAACUUCAUCUCAGACCUUCUGCUUGCUUCUCUGUAAGCCUGGAGAGAACUACCUGUCUUCUCAUCAAGUUGUUUUUAUUGGAGUUAGUGUAGCGAAAACUCUCAAACCGUGUUUUUUUCUACUCUCACACCACCACAAAAAUCAUCAUCAAUACAGAAGAAGACUUCUGUGACCAAAGGUAUGGGGGUUUUUCCCUACACACCAAGCAGUGCACAUCAGCUGGGUAUUCUCCAGUUCAAUUCUGGCACUGUCUACCUGGAGAAUUUAAGAACAUGCCAACCUAUCCUUAAGAUACCAGUCACAAGUCCGGGCCACCCCAUCCUUCAGACACCAGUUGCAAAUCUGGGCCUCUGGAACUUCUGACCAACUGGUUUCAAGUUGGGUUCCUCUUUGGGCCCACUUCCUCUUUGGGCUCAAUUAAUUUGCUGGAGUGGUGCACAGAACUCAGGGAAAUACUUGCUUACCUUUAGUGGUUUAUUAUAAAGGAUAUAUGUAGAGGAUACAGAUGAAGCGAUGCAUAGGGUGAAGUAUGGGGGAAGGGGUGCGGAGCUUUCAUGUCCUCCCUGGGUAUGCUACCCCCUGGGAACCUCCGUAUGUUCAGCUAUCCAGAAGCUCUCUGAACCAGUUUUCUUGGGUUUUUAAAGAAGCCUCAUGACAUCAACAUUCCUUCCUCCAGGGUAUGAGGCAGGACCCUCUCUGGAGGGUCUUAAGACCCACUGUCAGAGAGGCUGGGUAGAUUAAAGUCCUGCUAUAGAGCCGAUAAAAGGAGAAGAGGAGAAGGUCAGAGGCCUGCCUCUGAGGCCUCACACCCUCAGCAUUAUAACAAAAGACAAACAAGGGCUAUAGGGGUUAGGAGCCAGGAACCAUGAAUGAAAACCAAUGUAUAUGUAUCAUAAUGCUGCAGAGUUAAAUAAGCUAAUAUGAAAGAAAUCUGAUAAAUAUAGAGUAGCAAACAAUUUUAAAUUGCCUGAAUUAUUAUAUUCUAAUAGUAAACUGUAGGCAGUUAAAGAGAGGAACCUGAAUAACACAGAAGAUUCUGAUGCUAAAAAAUAAAUAGUUGAUCUUAGUUUCUGAGUAUCUAAGGUGUAUCAGAAGAAGAUAAGGAUGUGUGCAGCUUUUUUGAAAGUAGAUGCUUAAUGAAUAGUUAGCUACUAGUUAGUAUAUCCAAUGGCUACUUCUCAAGUAUUCCCUAGAAUUUUUUUAACUUAAAUUUUUGCCCCUUUUCUGGCUAAAGCUGUUUUUGAAGGUAUCAACUAGGUAUUAUAAGCUUUAGGGCUUUGUGUAGCUUACAAGGUAUGACAGAUACAUUUAUUCAAAUUAUUGACUGUUUUCUCAUAUACACUUUUUUUUUCCUUUCUUGGAAUAUCAUUCUUUUGAAGAACCCCAGGGUUUCACAUUGGGUGAAGUUUGGUUGUUAUUACCAAAAGAGAUAGCACAUUUCAUUGCUGAGAACCCUCAAGAGCAAGACUUCAUAUUUGGAGUAGAAUGAAAUUAAGAUGACACUAAAGAAUUUGACUUAUAAAAAACUAAUAUAUCCAUUCAAUGUCUUAGGUUAAUGUUCAUGGUGAGUCUGAGUAUGUUAAUAAACUGUAUUAGCUAUAGUUUCUGUAUCUCAUUACUAUUGGUUUGAAACUGGGUAUAUAUGCUUCUUAAAUUGUUGACAUUCACCUUUUUGUUUUGAGCUAGUCACUGUUAUCUGUCAUGUUAGACUUGGGGCCAUAGCUUUUUCUAAAUGAAAAGACUUAUCUUACCAUAUUUUUUUUCUUUUACAUAAGAGAUACUAUUAAUAUAUAUAAGCCUUGAAAGGAAAAGGAUACUAAUGUAUGUUGACUGUGUUACUAUGUACAAGCAUACCAAACAUUUAACAUUUGUAUCAUUUAAUUCUCCCUUCAACCUGGUGAGAGAGUAUUAUUGUCCCCAUUUUACAAAAGGAAACAUUGAAACAUAGAGAUUAAGUAAACAAAAUUACUAUAAUGGAGAAAUCCUGCUUUCUCCUUCCCUUUUACCCUCAGUGGGCAUUUUUCAUACCUGCUUUCAUUUAAUUAUACAACUCUUUGAAGAUGUUAUUAUCAUUUUGCAGAUGAAGAAAAACAUUAACAUGAAUGUACAAUUUAAAGAAUAAGAAAAUGAAAAUGUGUACUACAUUAAGGAAUAGAAGCCUAUAUAAAAGGUUUUCGUUUGGUUUUGUUUACAUCAAUUGAUUCUCAAAUGUUAAACCAACCUUGCUUUUUUUCAUAUCAACACUACUUGGGGCCGGCCAUGGUGGCUCACCUGUGCAAUCUCAGCACUUUGGGAGGCCCAGGCGGGUGGAUUGCUUGAAGUCAGGAGUUCGAGACCAGCUUGGCCAACAUGGUGAAACCCCGUCUCUACUAAAAAUACAAAAAAUUAGCCAGGCAUGGUGGCACGCACCUGUAGUCCCAGCUACUCAGGAGGCUGAGGCAGGAGAAUCACUUCAACCUGGGAGGCAGAGGUUGUAGUGAUCAGAGCUCGCCCCACUGCACUCCAGCCUGGGUGACAGAGCGAGACUCCAUCUCAAAAAACAAAAAACAACAACAACAAAAAAAUUAGCUGGGCCUGGUGGUGCAUGCCUGUAGUCCUAGCUACCCAGGAGUCUGAGGCAGAGAAUCACUUGAACUGGGAGGUGGAGGUUGCCAAGAUUGCCACUGCACUCCAGCUUGGGCGACAGAGUGAGACUCCGUCUCAAAACAAAAACAAAAAACAAAACAAAACAAAAAAACACAACUUGGUCAUGAGGUAUUGUACUUUUUACAUAUUGUUGGAUUUGAUUUAUGUCAUAUUAAGUAUUUUUACAUCUAUAUUCAUAGGAAAAUUGGUCUAUAGUUUUCUUAUAAUAUCUUAGUUUGGUUUUGAUACAGGGUCAUGGUGCCCUUUUAGAAUGACUUGAGAAGUGUUCUCUCUUCUUCAAUUUUCUGGAUAAGCCUUUUAGAAUUAGUAUUAUUUCUUCCUUAAAUGUUUGUUAGAAUUGACCAGUGAAGUCAGCUGGACCUGGAAGUUUUCUUUGUGGGGUGGUUUUUAACUGUAAUUUCAAUUCCUUUAAUAUAUGUAAGGUUAUUCAGGUUAUCUGUUUCUUCUUGAGUGAGCUUUAUAAUUUGUCUUUCAUGGAAUUUGUCUGUUUCAUCUAAGUUGUUAAAUCUAUUGACAUCAAGUUGCUCAUGACGUUCUCUUACCCUUUUAAUGUCUGUCUUUAAUUUAUCUCUCUCACUUGUGAUAUUGGUAAUUUAUGUAUUUUCUCUCCACCCCCCUCCUCCAUUAGUCUGGCUAGUGAUUUAUUAAUUUUAUUGAUCUCAGAGAGCCAGCAUUUGCUUUCAUUGACUCAAUAAAAAAUUUUAAAUAAACUUUAUUUUUUUAGAGCAGUUUUAGGUUCACAGCAAAAUUGAGUGGAAAAUACAGAGUUCUUAUAUCCCCCCCACCAGCCUUUCCCACUUCAACAUUUCACACCAGAAGUGGUAUAUUUGUUACAACUGAACCUACAGUGAUGUAUCAUUAUCACCCAAAGUCCAUAAUUUACAUUGGGGUUCACUCUUGAUGUUGUACAUUCUGUGGGUUUUGACAAAUGUGUAAUGGCAUAUAUCUACCAUUAUCAUAUUAUCAUACAAAAUAGUUCCACUCUCCUAAAAAUCCUCUGUGCUCCACCUGUUCAUCCCUACCUCCCAGUUAACCCCUGGCAACCACUGAUCUUUUCACUCUCUCCAUAGUCUUUGCCUUUUUCAAAGUUUCAUACAGUUGAAAUCAUAUAGUAUGUCACCUUUUCAGAUUGGCUUCUUUCACGUAGUAAUAUAUACGUUUAAGGUUCUUGCAUGUCUUUUCAUGCAUGGCAUGAUUGCUCAUUUCUCUUUAGCGCUGAAUCAUAUUCCAUUGUCUGGAUGUGCCACGGUUUAUUUAUCCAUUCACCUACUGAAGGACAUAUUGGUGGCUUCCAAGUUUGGGCAAUUAUGAAUAAAACUGCUAUAAACAUAAGGACAUACGUUUUCGACUCAUUUGGGUCACUACCAAGGAGCAUGAUUGCUGGAUCAUAUGAAUAUUAAAGGAGACAGGAAGAAGUCCAGAUGAAGUGACUCAUGGAACCAUUUGUUUAUCUGAACCUGAGCUAAAUCUUAGGAGAGAAGGGAAUUUGACAAGAAACUGAAGUUUUGAUUCAGAUAUAUUUUGAAUUGAAACCAGAGAUGUUCUAGAGUUUAGAUUCUUUCAUUUGAUUAAGCACUGUGAGGAACUAUAAGUUGUCAAAACCAGUAUGUAUGGAUUGAAGAGUGACAGAAAGGGUAAAUAUAUAGAUGAACUAUAUUAAUUGUAUCAGACAAUUUUUAUGAGCUCUAAAAUGUAUGUGGAAUUAAAACUCAUGAUAUCAGCAACUCAAAAAGUGGGAAGGGUAUACAUAAAGUGUUUUAAGGUCUUAGAGUUAGCUAUAAAGUGAUAGAAGUACUGAUUUGUAUUAGACUGUAAUUAGCAAGGAUGGUUUUAAUCAUUAGGGUAACCAUGAUUGAAACAGUAAAAGAAUUAUUAGCUGGCAAAAGAAAUUGAAUAAUGAAAACUACUUGAUAAAAUCAAAAGAAGGCAAGAGAGAAGAGAAAGAAUAUAAAACAGGUUAAUUGGAAGAAACAAACAAUAGGCUAAUGGAUAAAAUUUAAAAUAUAUUAAUGACAUCAAAUGUAAAUGGUUUAAAUAUUCUAGUAAAAGACAAAUUUGUUUGAAAAAUUUGGAAGACUAAAUUUCUUUCUUUUUCUUUUGAGUCAGAGUCUUGCUGUGUUACCCUGGCUGGAGUGGCACGAUCUCGGCUCCCUGCAACCUCUGCCUCCUUGGCUCAAGCAAUCCUCCCACCUCAGCCUCCCAAGUAGCUGGGACUACAGAUGCAUGCCACCACACCUAGCUAAUUUUCUUUAUUUUUUGUAGAGACAGAGUUUUGCCAUGUUGCCCAGGCUGGUCUCAAACUCCUGAGCUCAAACGAUUUGCCCACCUUGGCUUCCCAAAGUGCUGGGAUUAUAAAUUUCUUUAAAACCAAAAUAUAUUUCAUUUUCAAGGGAUACAUGUUACAUAUAAGAACACAAAAAGGUUGAAACUAAAAGGAUUAAAAUAUACCAUGCAAAUGCUAAUCAAAGGAAAGCUGAUGAAGCUAUGCUAAUAUCAGGCAAAGUAGACAUUAAGGCAAAAAGCAAUACUAGACGUAAAGAAGGUCAUUUCAUAAUAAUAUAAAAGGUCCAUACACUGGAAAGACAUAAUAAUUCUAAAUUCAUGUGAACUUAAUAAUUUGGCUUUAAAGAAAUAAAGCAAAAUAUGACAGAGCUAAAAUGAGUAUGGCCACAAAUUUCAUUUCUCUAGAAGCUAAACCAGAGAGUCUAGCUGUGUGAUUUAGAACAAAUGAAGUGAGCCCACAAUGUUUCCAGGCCAUAGCACAGGAAGAGGGAACCCAAACAGCUCAGGAAUUACAAAGGUUUGAGUUUGGGUUCAGAGAUGACAAGGAAUGAAAAUUAUAUCAGAUGGAAAUUUGCAUCUACAAAAAUAAAUGAAGAGCCCUGGAAAUGGUAUGGUCUGAAUAUGCGUUGCUUGGCAGCUCGGGUCAACUAUAAGACUUUGAUUAUUAUCUGCGCACUCUUCACUUUGGUCACAGUACUUUUGUGGAAUAAGUGUUCCAGUGACAAAGCAAUCCAGUUUCCACGGCGUUCGAGUAGUGGCUUCAGAGUGGAUGGGUUUGAAAAAAGAGCAGCAGCAUCUGAGAGUAACAACUAUAUGAACCACGUGGCCAAACAACAGUCUGAGGAAGCAUUCCCUCAGGAACAGCAGAAAGCACCCCCUGUUGUUGGGGGCUUCAAUAGCAAUGUGGGAAGUAAGGUGUUAGGGCUCAAAUAUGAAGAAAUUGACUGUCUCAUAAAUGAUGAACACACAAUUAAAGGGAGACGAGAGGGGAACGAAGUCUUUCUUCCAUUCACUUGGGUUGAGAAAUAUUUUGAUGUUUAUGGAAAGGUGGUUCAGUAUGAUGGCUAUGAUCGGUUUGAAUUCUCUCAUAGCUAUUCCAAAGUCUAUGCACAGAGAGCCCCCUAUCACCCCGAUGGUGUGUUUAUGUCUUUUGAAGGCUACAAUGUGGAAGUCCGAGACAGAGUCAAGUGCAUAAGUGGGGUUGAAGGUGUGCCAUUAUCUACACAAUGGGGACCUCAAGGCUAUUUCUAUCCAAUCCAGAUUGCACAGUAUGGAUUAAGUCAUUACAGCAAGAAUCUAACUGAGAAACCUCCUCACAUAGAGGUAUAUGAAACAGCAGAAGACAGAGACAAAAACAAGCCUAAUGACUGGACUGUGCCAAAGGGCUGCUUUAUGGCGAAUGUGGCUGAUAAGUCUAGAUUCACCAAUGUCAAACAGUUUAUUGCACCAGAAACCAGUGAAGGUGUAUCCUUGCAACUGGGAAACACAAAAGAUUUUAUUAUUUCAUUUGACCUCAAGUUCUUGACAAAUGGAAGUGUGUCCGUGGUUCUAGAGACCACAGAAAAGAAUCAGCUCUUCACUAUACAUUAUGUCUCAAAUGCUCAGCUAAUUGCUUUUAAAGAAAGAGAUAUAUACUAUGGCAUUGGGCCCAGAACUUCAUGGAGCACAGUUACCAGGGACCUGGUCACUGACCUCAGGAAAGGAGUGGGUCUUUCAAACACAAAAGCUGUCAAGCCAACCAAAAUAAUGCCCAAGAAGGUGGUUAGGUUGAUUGCAAAAGGUAAGGGAUUCCUCGACAACAUUACCAUCUCUACCACAGCCCACAUGGCUGCAUUUUUUGCUGCUAGUGAUUGGCUAGUAAGGAACCAGGAUGAGAAAGGUGGCUGGCCAAUUAUGGUGACCCGUAAGUUAGGGGAAGGGUUCAAGUCUUUAGAGCCAGGAUGGUAUUCUGCCAUGGCCCAAGGGCAAGCCAUUUCUACAUUAGUCAGGGCCUAUCUGUUAACAAAAGACCAUAUAUUCCUCAAUUCAGCUUUAAGGGCAACAGCCCCUUAUAAGUUUCUAUCUGAGCAGCAUGGAGUUAAAGCUGUGUUUAUGAAUAAACAUGACUGGUAUGAAGAAUAUCCAACCACACCUAGCUCUUUUGUUUUAAAUGGCUUUAUGUAUUCUUUAAUUGGGCUGUAUGACUUAAAAGAAACUGCAGGGGAAAAACUCGGAAAAGAAGCAAGGUCCUUGUAUGAGCGUGGCAUGGAAUCUCUUAAAGCCAUGCUGCCCUUGUAUGACACUGGCUCAGGAACCAUCUAUGACCUCCGUCACUUCAUGCUUGGCAUCGCUCCUAACCUGGCUCGCUGGGACUAUCAUACCACCCACAUCAAUCAGUUGCAGCUACUCAGUACCAUUGAUGAGUCCCCAGUCUUCAAAGAAUUUGUCAAGAGGUGGAAAAGCUACCUUAAAGGCAGCAGGGCAAAGCACAACUAGAGCUCACAACCAAAACUGCACUUCAGCCUCUGCUGUACACAGAAACUACAGGCUCUGUCUCAGGAGAGCAUAGGCACAUUUUAAAAGGUUAUGUACUAGGUUUUUGUGGAUUCUAUCAAAGUGAUAAGUGAUCCUUAAAACCAGCCUUCUAAAAUAAUUGCAUUCCAUGGGUUGGGUAUUUAGAAAUGUAGGUGGCAUUUAGAACACAAUGUUUAAUCAAUGGGCUGAACAAAGAUGCUUCACUUUGCCUUGCCCAUCACCCUAUACAGUUUCGCAGAUAGUCUAGUCACUCUAUGUGAGAAAGAUAAUGGUAAGUAGUUGCUACUGGCCAACUGUCUAGCACUUACCUGAAAACUUAGUAUGGAGCUCUUUUAAAAUGUGAUUAUUUAUAUUUAUGUUGAAAGCGGACUUUAAAAAAAAUAAUGUGCUGUAACACAGUAAAUAUGUACUUGUAGCCUGGAUAGCAGACUGUGUUCAACUUUUUAAAAAGAUGUUUCCUUUCUAAAGAUUAAUUUCUUGGGAGCAAAUGAGUAUUUGUUGCAUUUGUUCAAUUUGUUGUAUAUGGUGAAUAUUUAAUUAUGGUUUUCUUGAAACGUGUAAAUUAAAAACACAAUCAGUGUUCAGGCUUCAGUUAUAUAAUGUAAGCACAACUAAAAUGAAACUUGUUGACUGCACAAGAAAUUACAAAAAUGUUUCUGUUUUGAAACUUGAUCUACAAUCAGUAAAAGUUUGAUAAUCAGUAUAUCCCUUCCCAACCCCCAUUGUGACAGUUUCUUUUUGUCACUGUCUAGAAUUUUGUAUUUUAUUUCAGACUAUACCUUGGAGUUUUGUAUAUUUUGAGAGAGAUAUUUUUGGGACAUUAUUUUGGAAACUUAUUACAAAUCUAAAUUUGGAAAGGAGCUAGUAGCUUUAAGGCCACCACCAUAUUUUACUUUUUUAGGAUUUUUCCCCCUUUAAAUAAAAAUAUUAGAUCAAAUACUAUAUGCAAGAAAUCAUAGCAAAGUUUUUUUUUCCUACCAAGAUCAUUCUUGAUCAUCAGCUUCCCAAACUAGUAAGUCUGUGCAUCAUUGGGUGUUUUUUUUUAAUUUAAUUUUAAAUUAUCCCAGCUAUUAGAUAGAAGGGAUGUUACUGCACUUAUGUGUAAUCAGAUCUUUAUUUAGGUAUACAUAUCCUCCUAUACCGCACAUAAAUAGAUUUCAGAGCCCCCAUACAAUGGGCAGUGUCUGCUAUAGGGCUUCAGGCAUUAAAUAAAACCGAGGGUUGUUGAUUUUGCUGUGACAGUACACUAAAUCAAUACUAUAUCUUAUACAGUUUGAAAAUAUGAUACCCUACACUUUCAGGGGACCGAGUCUGACAAACACAAUACAUUUAUCUGUGACCUAUAUCAAGUACACAUUUAGGAGCCAGGUAGGUUACCUGCUUACACACUAUAUUUUAAUUGAAUUCAAACUAUCAAGCACUACUUAGAAACUGGAAAACAUAUAUAUGUUAGCAUCAAAGGGGGCAGAAGCAAAGAAGAUACAGAUCUGCACUGAAGACAUUAGACUGGCCAUAGAAAAGUAAGCUUGAACUCCCAAUUGAUGUGACCACACUCUUCUUAAUUUUGUUCACAGUAAAAACACUUUUUUGAGUUAUUAGGCUUACCCCUAGCUUUUGACCUUUGCAUUUCAUAUAUGUUAGAUGUCUCAGCAAGAAUAUCUGGUCUCCCCUAAUUUUUAUUCCCAGUGCCGAUGUUCAAAAUAAACUUUCUCCAGUCUGGGAACCUUUUUUACUUCCCCAUAUUUGUUAUUAUUUAGAAUGGUUCAUACGUCUGCUUUGUUUGCAUACUGGUCUUCAGAUUAUGAGACUCGAUGAUAACAGUAUGGUACUGCUUCUGUGACAAAUAUCGUGCCUUAACAAUGUGGCUGUCCUUUUCCACUGAAGAAGGAAAGACGUUUUGAUCUAGAAAUAGCGUUGUGAUUUCCUUGCUGUUGGUUUUACACUGCCUUCCACAUUGCAACAGCAAGUUGAUUUCUUGUGAUCCCAGAAUUUUCUAAGAGGAUGAGUUGAAUCUAUAGCAGCAUUGUCAGUACAGACCAGUGGUUCUCAAACUUUAAAAUGCCUCAGCAUCACUUGGGAGCUUAUUGAAAUGCAGAUCCCAGAGUCAGUAAAUCUGCCUGUGAAGUAUGAUAGUCUGCAUUUGUAAUGAGCAUUCAAGUGAUUCUGAUGCAGGUGAGCUGGGGGCAUACAGGGAGGAACACUGCCCUGGACUAUCCAUUGCAUUUUUGCCUCUAAACAACUACAGAAUUUUCUAGGGUUUUAAAUUAUGUAAAAUGUUUACUUAUUCUGAGCUUAGAGAGAAUGGGGAGGGUAUUUUUAAAUUUUAUUGUUUUAUUUCUUUAAGUUUUUCUUUGCUUUAAGAUUAUAGGUAUUAGGUUUGUUUUUGUUUUUCCACUUAUCUUGAGUUCACUUUGAUGUUAAAUCUAUUGCUACUUCAGUUGUAAAACCAGCCAAAAGUUUCUGGAUGAAGGUCAAGUUUGACCUUUUAGGAGUUAUUGUACAUAAAGGCUUCAUCCACGAACCAUCCAGCGCACAGAAGCAAGUGCAAAAAUGACACAAGCACAACUCUCCAGACGUGGCUCCUUCUCCUUUCUCAGUGCAGACUCUCACUGAAAGCUGCUAUUUUCAUCCUCCUUGUGGUUGCUUUUCUUGUUUCUCUUCCAUUGUACAUGUGGGUUAUAUACCAUAUGUUAAAUAUGCAAUAAAGUGUUUACAGGAUGCCCUUCUGAAGGGUAGUCCUUUGUAAAGCUGUACAGACUUUGCAGUUUAAGCACAAUGUGCACAUGUUAGUUUUAUAUACAGCAAAACUUGAUUUUUUGCAGAUGGAAAGGUAUUUUGUUUCUAUACAAAGUAAAUGGAUUGUUUGUGCUUAAUGUAAAGCCGCUUUAUAAAACUGUAAAAUAAAGUUUUUUUCUUAAAAAGAA